GCGGUGCGCGCGCUGGCCCGGCAGCAUGGCGGCGGCGGCGGGCGCCCCUCCGCCGGGUCCCCCGCAACCGCCUCCGCCGCCGCCGCCCGAGGAGUCGUCCGACAGCGAGCCCGAGGCGGAGCCCGGCUCCCCACAGAAGCUCAUCCGCAAGGUGUCCACGUCGGGUCAGAUCCGACAGAAGACCAUCAUCAAAGAGGGGAUGCUGACCAAACAGAACAAUUCAUUCCAGCGAUCAAAAAGGAGAUACUUUAAGCUUCGAGGGCGAACGCUUUACUAUGCCAAAACGGCAAAGUCAAUCAUAUUUGAUGAGGUGGAUCUGACAGAUGCCAGCGUAGCUGAAUCCAGUACCAAAAACGUCAACAACAGUUUUACGGUAAGAUCUCAGUCAUGC